GCUGUGUUUUCCGGCGCUUUCUCCGCGCCGCCAAACCCGUUUUCUUCCUGGUGGCGUUUGGGCUUAAUACAGCUUUGGCGAGGUCGGAUGACGGGUGGGAGCCAGCGGUGGAAGGGGUGGCGAAAGUACCGGUUUGCCCCAGGCCGCCGAGGGGCCUCCUUAGAGAGACCUUGCCUGCUCCGCUCGCGUCCGCCGGGGCCGCGCGGGUCCUCCUGGCGCCGCCAGGUUCAAAAAGCCACUCGAGUUGUCACUGCGACGGCCCUGGGCCAGGAGCCGUUUCGGGAUCUGUCAAACAACGAGUUUUCGUCGUUCGAAUCAGGUUGACUGGUCCUUCAUCCCCCCAAUCUCCCGUACCUGGCGAGUCCAGCUCGUCGCGGCCUGUACCUCCCCACAGAGCUUCAAAACGGGCUUUUAGGAAGAAGGAAUGGAGGCUUUGAAGCAAUGCUAAGAAAAGAGUGAUAUGCAAGCUGAGACCAAAAAUAUGGUAUGAUUUAGCCAUACUGAAGGGGAAGGAAAUAAGAGCUGGGCAAAGCAUUCUGUGAAUUGGCUGACUCCACUUCUAUGGUGAGAGAGAGGAGUGCAUCAAAGAUUACUCCCAGUAGAGAUGGUUUCAGCAUGUUGGCCAGUCUGGUCUCAGACUCCUGACCUCAAGUGAUCCACCCACCUCGGCCUCCCAAAAUGCUGGGAUUACAGGUAUAAGCCACUGUGCCUGGCCAAAGAUACCGUUAACCCUGGAUAAAGAGAAUGGAGGUUACCUCUGUCCGUGUAGAUUCCUAAGCUGUCCUGGAGUGAUCCUUGGAGUAAAGGAAAGGUGCUUUGAAGCACAUUCAGCCAUCAGCCCUGUGGGAUGGCAGCCACUGAUUUGUCCUAUGGUCUUUACAGGGACCCAGUCUGCCUUCAAGAAAAGACAGAAGUAGAAAGGGUGGUGGCUGACUGUCUGACAAAUUGUUAUCAGGUAUGCAGGAAGUAUAUCCUUCUCCAAAAUAUCAUACUUGCAUCACCAGGUAGACACAUUUCCUUCUACACAGAAUUAUCUUCAGAGCUUCUUAAAGCAAAUAAAGCCUCCUUCAAGGACUGAGUCCCUAGUCGAAUUCCCGGAAGGAGUGGAGCCUGUCAUAUUGGUGAGGGUUUGCCUUGAAUGUCAUCCCAGUAUUUCAAUAUUGAUUAAUUAGUCUUCCCUCAUGGUCCCAACUGCAUAGUUUUUAUUUUGUUGAGUGUUCUGACACAUGGUAAGGGACAUGAAAGUAUCCUUUGAGAUAAUCUUUCCAUUCAUCAGUGUUUAUCUAGCAUCUGCUCAAGAGUGUGCUGCAGUGGAGGGAAAUCAGAUGACCUCCCAGUCUGGUUGUGUUACAUACAAUCAUGUGUAAGAAGUGCCAUUCAAGCCGUGUCACUGGAGGGGACUGACAGUGAGUGAGUGUGGAUAGAGAGGACCUCCUGGGGUGGGCAAUGUGAGCCCUCAGACUCUGUAGGUAUUGCAUUUUGCAGUGAACACUGGUAGACAUGUUUUGUGGCUCAAGCCAGCAUGUGUGUGAUGGUUUAGGAUUCAGUGACUUUUGAUGAUCUGGCUGUGGACUUCACCCCAGAAGAAUGGACUUUACUGGACCCAACUCAGAGAAACCUCUACAGAGAUGUGAUGCUGGAGAACUACAAGAAUUUGGCCACAGUAGGAUAUCAGCUCUUCAAACCCAGUCUGAUCUCUUGGCUGGAACAAGAAGAGUCUAGGACAGUGCAGAGAGGUGAUUUCCAAGCUUCAGAAUGGAAAGUGCAACUUAAAACCAAAGAGUUAGCCCUUCAGCAGGAUGUUUUGGGGGAGCCAACCUCCAGUGGGAUUCAAAUGAUAGGAAGCCACAACGGAGGGGAGGUCAGUGAUGUUAAGCAAUGUGGAGAUGUCUCCAGUGAACACUCAUGCCUUAAGACACAUGUGAGAACUCAAAAUAGUGAGAACACAUUUGAGUGUUAUCUGUAUGGAGUAGACUUCCUUACUCUGCACAAGAAAACCUCUACUGGAGAGCAACGUUCUGUAUUUAGUCAGUGUGGAAAAGCCUUCAGCCUGAACCCAGAUGUUGUUUGCCAGAGAACGUGCACAGGAGAGAAAGCUUUUGAUUGCAGUGACUCUGGGAAAUCCUUCAUUAAUCAUUCACACCUUCAGGGACAUUUAAGAACUCACAAUGGAGAAAGUCUCCAUGAAUGGAAGGAAUGUGGGAGAGGCUUUAUUCACUCCACAGACCUUGCUGUGCGUAUACAAACUCACAGGUCAGAAAAACCCUACAAAUGUAAGGAAUGUGGAAAAGGAUUUAGAUAUUCUGCAUACCUUAAUAUUCACAUGGGAACCCACACUGGAGACAAUCCCUAUGAGUGUAAGGAGUGUGGGAAAGCCUUCACCAGGUCUUGUCAACUUACUCAGCACAGAAAAACUCACACUGGAGAGAAACCUUAUAAAUGUAAGGAUUGUGGGAGAGCCUUCACUGUUUCCUCUUGCUUAAGUCAACAUAUGAAAAUCCAUGUGGGUGAGAAGCCUUAUGAAUGCAAGGAAUGUGGGAUAGCCUUCACUAGAUCUUCUCAACUUACUGAACAUUUAAAAACUCACACUGCAAAGGAUCCCUUUGAAUGUAAGAUAUGUGGAAAAUCCUUUAGAAAUUCCUCAUGCCUCAGUGAUCACUUUCGAAUUCACACUGGAAUAAAACCCUAUAAAUGUAAGGAUUGUGGGAAAGCCUUCACUCAGAACUCAGACCUUACUAAGCAUGCACGAACUCACAGUGGAGAGAGGCCCUAUGAAUGUAAGGAAUGUGGAAAGGCCUUUGCCAGAUCCUCUCGCCUUAGUGAACAUACAAGAACUCACACUGGAGAGAAGCCUUUUGAAUGUGUCAAAUGUGGGAAAGCCUUUGCUAUUUCUUCAAAUCUUAGUGGACAUUUGAGAAUUCACACUGGAGAGAAGCCCUUUGAGUGCCUGGAAUGUGGUAAAGCAUUUACGCAUUCCUCCAGUCUUAAUAAUCACAUGCGGACCCACAGCGCCAAAAAACCAUUCACGUGUAUGGAAUGUGGCAAAGCUUUUAAGUUUCCCACGUGUGUUAACCUUCACAUGCGGAUCCACACUGGAGAAAAACCCUACAAAUGUAAACAGUGUGGGAAAUCCUUCAGUUACUCCAAUUCGUUUCAGUUACAUGAACGAACUCACACUGGAGAGAAACCCUAUGAAUGUAAGGAGUGCGGGAAAGCCUUCAGUUCUUCCAGUUCCUUUCGAAAUCAUGAAAGAAGGCAUGCGGAUGAGAGACUGUCAGCAUAAGGAAUGUGGGAAAACCUAAAGGUGUCCCUGUUCUCUCUGAAGACAUGAAAACUCACUGGGGAGAAACCCUAUGAAUGUAAAAAUGUGGAAGCAACUUUGUAUCUCAGGUCUUAAUGAACACAUAUGAAUUCACAGUGGAGAAGACCCUGCAUCAGGGAAUGUGGAAAUGACUUUGCUGAAUUCUCAAGCCUUACCAAACACAUCAGAAAUCUCACUGGAGAGAAACUGUAUGAAUGUAGAGAAUCUGGGAAUACCUUUCUGAAUCCCACAAACCUUAAUGUGUGUAUGUGAACUCACAUUGGAGAGAAACCCUGCAAUUUAAAUGGUAUGGUCUGGAUGAUGCCCCACUCCAUAUUUGUAAGCCCUAAGUCCUAGUUCCUUACACUAUAACUGUAUUUGGACAUAGGGUUUUCAAACAGGUGAGUAACUUCAAAUGAGGUUGUUGGGUUCGAUCCCUAAUCUGACAUCACUGGUGUCCCUAUAAGGGAAACUGAAGGAAGGAUACACAUGGAGAAGACUGUGUGGAUCCACCAGAAGAUGGCCAUCUACAAGCCAAGGACAGAGACCUGGAACAGAUGCUUUCAUUAUGGCCUCCAGAGGAAACCAACCCUGUCUCCACCUUGAUAUUGCACUUCCAGGCUCCAGAACUGUGAGGCAAUAAAUUUCUCUUGGUUAAAUCAUUCAGUCUGUUAUUUUGUACAGCAACCCUAGGAAACUAAUACUGUGAGGAACUUGGGAAAAGCUUUAGAUCAAGCUUGUCCAACCCGCAGGCCAGGAUGGCUUUGAAUGCAGACCAACACAAAUUUUUAAGCUUUCUUCAAACAUAAUAAAAUUUUUUUGUGAUUA